UGAUUCCACCCACUUUUUUCUUUCUCUUUUAAAUUUCUAGCCAUUCCUUCCAGAAAAAUUCCAUCCUCCAGAUAUUGAAGUUAGAUGCUGUACAAGCCAAUGUACAGUCCAGCUUUGCUCAGUCUGCUCUCCCUUCCAUGGCUGAAGUUCUAUGAUUCUGCUCUGUUAGUUAGCACUGAUGGAAUCACCUGUAGCUACAGCUUAAGGAAGGAAGGAAGAAAGGAAAGAAGGAAGGGAAGGACGGAGGGGAGGAGGGAGGGAAAGGGAAAGAAAAGGAAAGGGGGAGGGAGGGAGGGAAAGGAAAGAGGGAGGGAAGGAGGGAGGGAGAGAGGAAGGAAGGAAGGCAGGGAGGAGGGAGGGAGAGAGGAAGGAAGGAAGGCAGGGAGGAGGGAGGGAGGGAAAGAGAAAGGAAAUGCAUAGGGCAUUGUAACUUCCCCACAAAAAUAGAGCUUUUGAGAAAAUAGCAGCCUACUUUGUUCAUUUAUUCUUUGAUUCAAUCAGUCACAGAAACAUUUAUCAGGUAUUUACUGAAAGCCAGACACUUUGCCAGGUUCACAAAUACAGAAAUGAUUAAAAACCAACUGCUGCCUUCAAGGCGUUCCUAGUCAAGUAGACAAAGAGUUACAGUAGUGUGUGGGCCAUAGCUAAGAUCAUCCUAUCGCUUAUUGCAGAGCAGCCCUCUAAGCUUAGAUGAAGAAUUGUAAGGCUUAACCACAGACGCCUCAUAUCAUAGCUGGCUGGAUCUGCGAAAGAAAGCCGAGGUGCAAUUAGGAAGAAAUGUGGAAAUCCCCAGACUGCCACUGGGGUUGUUGGUACCAGUCUGUAUCCUUGCCUAAUCUGUUUUCAUUGAUCCACAUUGGCCUCUGACUUUGCCCCUCAGCUCUUGCUACAUGUUUGUAUUUGAAAAGCCACGGGUAAGUGGAGGUUCAGUCUUUCUUUUUUUUUUUUUUUUGAGACGGAGUCUCUGUCUGUUGCCCAGGCUGGAGUGCAGUGGUGUAGCAUGAUCUCGGCUCACUGCAACCUCCGCCUCCUGGGUUCAAGGGAUUCUCCUGCCUGAGCCUCCCGAGUAACUGGGAUUAUAGGCACCCACCACCACAUCCAGCUAAUUUUUUGUAUUUUUAGUAGAGACAGGGUUUCACCAUGUUGCCAGGCUGGUCUUGAACUCCUUACCUCAGGCAAUCUGCCCGCCUUGGCCUCCCAAAGUGCUGGGAUUACAGAUGUGAGCCACUGCACCCGGGCCAGGUUCAGCCUUUCUUCCAGGCAUCCUUUCACUUAACCCCAGAGAGGCUUUUAUCACACCACGCAAUUGAAAAGCUACCUUAAGUUCUCUCCCUUCACUUCUUCAGCUUUCCCAUAUCUUGGUAUUUUGUUUGGGGAUCCCUAGUUGUGGAAAUACCUAGAGUAACCAGAAAACCUUUCAACUGAACAUGAUUUCAUCUUUAAAGGACUAACUUCAGGACUGAUAGCAUAACAGAAAGCAUAUGAGGAAGAGUUAGAAACUUGUUACAUCUGGUCACAUUGAAACUUCAGUUGUUUUGCAUUUUUUGUUGGAGUGGUGGUUAAUUUUUUUCAACUAGUCUCACGUCUUAAUGAUUGAGGUACCAAAAGGGAAUGAAGGAAAUGAGCAAACUUGCAGUCAAGUCAGAGAAUCAUAGAUGAGAUACGAAAGAGGCCUUACAGCACCAUUCAUCCAACCUUGUUUCACAGAUAAGGAAACAGAGAAGUCCACUGAUUUGUGUUAAGUCACACAACUGGUCAGCGGAAAUAUUCAUAAAUAACUCUGUGUAAGACAUACCCAACCAUUAUACCAUUAAAAAAGGGAACUUUCAGUGAUAUGCUUCUUAGGAACAUCUUUAUCGUAGGUAGAAAUCAUACAUGAAGUGGCCAGGCACAGUGGCUCAUGCCUGUAAUCCCAGCACUUUAGGAGGUGGGGCUGGCGGACCACUUGAGAUCAGGAGUUGAGACCAGCCUGGCCAACAUGGUGAAACCGUGUCUACUAAAAAUACAAAAAUUAGCCGGGCGUGGUGGCACGCACCUGUAAUCCCACCUACUUGGGAGGCUGAGUCACGAGAAUUGGUUGAACCCAAGAGGCGGAGGUUGCAGUGAGCCAAGAUCACGCCACUGCAUUCCUGCCUGGGCGACAGAGUGAAACUGUGUCUCAAAAAAAAAAAAGAAAACAACCAAAAAAAAAAAAAAAAAGGAAAAGAAAAAUAACACGUGAAGUAUUGUAUUGUGUUUCAGAACUUGAAUUCCCAUCCCACUUUGCCUCCACGUGAUCAGGGAAGACCUGCCCCCCGCCCCGCCCCAACUAGAAAGAGACUAAACAUAAGCACAGUCCAAGGAAAUCACACAACACCCAGGUGUUGGGGCACAGAGGUGGAGCGGUCAGGCCCUGCCCUCCAUGGGGCAGGAACAGCUUGUCUGUUGUGCCUUCGCUGCUUCCUCAGUCCAUACUGUCACCAGUCCAAUGUGGAGGAGGCUGGAAGGAACUACCCCAACCAUUUCUUCCAUGUGUAGUAUGAUUUCAUGGGAAGGAUUAUUCCUUUUUAGUGCAUUGUUUGGCUAUUGUAAGUGCUGGCUGAGUUCGAAAUGCAGCAUUGGCUGAAUCAGUCCAGCCUCUCAUUUCCCUGAAUAGGUUACCAAACUCCAAAUAUAAGCCAAUGAUCAGGGGACGAUAAGAGGGAAGUGACCAGAUUCUACUUUGGGAGUGUAAAUAGGGUAAAUAGGGAGUGUAAAUGUUGGAUAUCAGGUGCAGACUGAACUUUAACCUGCAUAGGAGUUCAGAACUAGACAAGAGAUUGGAAGAAGGGGGCUGUCCUUGGAAGCAGCUGGCCAGAGUAUACCCCUGGAGAUCUACUGGAAAACUUGGUGUACGUGGUUGGGAAUGAACCUUUAACAGUUUUGAUGGAUUCCCUGCUUCCAGUCCUGGGAGUGCUUUUUCUUCUCUACUGUUUUACUAAGCAGAGUGUGUCUCACAUAAGGUCACUUUGCCAAGAAAUCUUAUUAUGGAUUCUGGGGAAGCUGGAAAGGAAGAAGGCAAUUGCCAGCCUGAAAGGAUUUGCAGGGUUGGACAAAGCUGUGCCCUCUCUCCAUUCUCUGUGUCAGUUUAGAGUUGCCACUCAAGGUGGCAUUAUGAUUACCAUCAAAGAGGCCAUUAGUGAUGAAGAUGAAGAUGAAGCCCUGUACCAGAAGGUAUCCUCUGAGCAGGGCCGGGUGGAGCAUCUCGGGGACUUGCUGUCCCACUGCCAGGAAUGCGGUUUGGCAGGAGACUUCUUCAUCUUCUGUUUGAAAGAGUUGACUCAUGUGGCCUCGGAAAAUGAAACAGAGUUAAAAACUGAGCCCUUCUCCAGCAAGAGCCUCUUGGAAUUAGAGCAACAUCAGACUCUUCUUGUGGAAGGCCAAGAGCGGAAGCUGCUUGUCCUGCAGCUGAUGGCUGUUCUGUGCGAGAGAAUGUCUGAGCAGAUAUUCACAAACGUCACUCAGGUGGUGGACUUUGUAGCAGCAACAUUGCAGAGAGCCUGUGCAAGCCUGGCCCAUCAGGCAGAGAGCACCGUGGAAUCACAGACGCUGAGCAUGUCCAUGGGGCUGGUGGCUGUCAUGCUAGGAGGAGCUGUUCAGUUGAAGUCAAGUGAUUUUGCUGUUCUGAAGCAGUUGUUGCCUCUGUUGGAGAAGGUAUCCAACACAUACCCUGAUCCGGUCAUCCAAGAACUCGCUGUUGAUCUCCGCAUCACCAUCUCUACCCAUGGAGCCUUUGCCACUGAGGCCGUCAGCAUGGCUGCCCAAAGUACACUGAACAGAAAAGAUCUGGAAGGGAAAAUAGAAGAGCAGCAACAAACCAGUCAUGAAAGACCCACUGAUGUAGCUCAUAGCCACCUUGAACAACAGCAGAGCCAUGAGACAGCCCCCCAGACAGGCCUGCAGUCAAAUGCUCCAAUCAUUCCUCAAGGAGUCAAUGAGCCCAGCACUACUACAAGUCAGAAAUCUGGAAGCGUAACCACAGAACAGCUCCAAGAGGUUCUUUUGUCAGCUUAUGACCCUCAAAUUCCAACACGGGCUGCUGCCCUGCGUACUCUUUCCCACUGGAUAGAGCAGAGAGAAGCAAAAGCCCUUGAGAUGCAAGAGAAGCUUCUCAAGAUAUUCUUGGAAAACUUGGAACAUGAAGACACUUUUGUAUAUCUAUCUGCAAUUCAGGGGGUUGCCCUGCUGUCAGACGUCUAUCCUGAGAAAAUCUUGCCGGACUUGUUGGCUCAAUAUGACAGCAGCAAAGACAAGCACACACCAGAGACCAGAAUGAAAGUCGGGGAAGUCCUUAUGCGAAUCGUCAGGGCAUUAGGAGACAUGGUCUCAAAGUACCGAGAACCUUUGAUCCAUACCUUCCUGAGGGGAGUGAGAGAUCCUGAUGGUGCUCACAGGGCCAGCAGCUUGGCCAACCUUGGGGAGCUGUGCCAGAGGCUGGACUUUCUGCUGGGCUCCGUGGUCCAUGAGGUAACAGCUUGCCUGAUUGCUGUGGCCAAAACAGAUGGUGAAGUUCAAGUACGCAGAGCUGCCAUACAUGUGGUUGUGCUGCUGCUUCGGGGACUCAGCCAGAAAGCUACUGAGGUGCUGAGCGCCGUCCUCAAGGAUCUCUACCACCUGCUGAAGCACGUAGUGUGUCUGGAGCCCGAUGACGUGGCCAAGCUCCAUGCCCAGUUGGCCCUAGAAGAGCUGGAUGACAUCAUGAAAAACUUCCUGUUCCCUCCACAGAAGCUGGAGAAGAAGAUCAUGGUCCUGCCGUAGACCUGGCUCCAAGGACGUGGAGGAGGCAGGCAGGGCCAGGCACCCAGAGCCGUGCCCAGGUCUUCCAGCAGGUGGCCCUGCUGCCUCUUGAGUGCUGGCAGCAUGGCUGACCCUCGGGGUGGUUUUAUGGUGCAGGUCACUUGGGUCUUCAGGGUCCCUUCCGAGGGCAUGUGUUCAGCACUCCCGCGUUCAGCCUGAGGGGUGUACAGUUAAGAGAAGACAGUUACAGAUCUCAUUAAUCUACAUUUUUCACUGUCCUCUAGCAUUGAAAGAAGGAUGUCUACCUGGUGAAAGUAUAUUUUAACAUGACUGAUGGAAUUUCACUAAUUGCCCACUCUCUUGGAACUUGAGGAGAAGCGGUUGGCCACCCAUAUGUCACCUAGCUCUAUAUUCUUUCAGGCUGAGAUUCUUCUUCAGGAAAAUGAGGAGCAGAACUGGCCACCCUUGGCUGCUCAAGAGGCAUUUCAGAGUAGGAGAUGCAGUUGGAGGUGGGGAGGGGAAGGAAAUAGUUAUCAAAUAAUGCAAAAUGGAAUAAAGUUAUCUUGGAUGGAAAGAACAGGGCUAAAUCUGGUCCUCUGGUGUCGAGAUGGAAAACUGUGGAGUUGAAGAGGCUCUGAUGCCCAGAAAGGACAAUCAAGCUGGUUGACUCUUCCAGAGAAGAAGGGUAAGCCCUGUAUUUAUCCUCCCAGGCCAUUCUUCUUCACUCCUGCUGCUGUUUGCAGAGAGUUGCCCUGAUUAUCAGGAGAAAAGAACCACGAGCAUCCAGAGAGUUUACAUCCUGCCUUCUGUCCUCUGCUCCUUCAGAAAGAUGAAUGCCUAGACAAUGGGUUCACACUGAAUGCAGGCUGGAAAGAAUGCAUGCUGGUGGCCUAAUGCCAGGGCUGUUGAAACAAUUUCAGAUAUAGCACUGUGGUCUCCACUUUAUUUCUUUAUAUGUUUUGGCCGCUGCAUUUUGAUUGCAGCUAAAAGAGAUAACAGAAAGGAGAUACUGGCUGGCUGCUUCAUAUUAGCCCUCUCUGUUGUCAACACCUUGAUGAGGCCAACCCAGAGAUGCUUGAUCAGUCCUCAGCUUUGCAGGGCUAGGUACAGAAUUUUAUCACAGGAUUUUAUCACGCUCUCUGGGGUGACUAGAUCCACAGGAACCAAAACGCAGUUUCCAAAAGCUCGAGUGACUGAAGGAUCUAUACACAAACAUGGCUAUUUGCUAGUUAACAACAGGAUAUUUCUCUCUGGCCAGAUCACAGACAUGGUUCUGAGUCAGAUCUUCCUUGGUGGCAUCCCUUUAAAGAGGCCAUCUUAUGAACAGGAUCACAAGUGAGCUUAGUGAGCAGAGAGUUAGAACAAAUCUAGCUAGGUGUGUUUAAGGAAUAUUUCCAUUCAGCUAGUGUAGCUGGAUUAAUUUCUAUUCUCCAAAUCAAGGAUGUCUAGAAAAUGGGCAUUGUGGCUUUCAAAUCUAAGAAGAAUCUCCUUUGGGCCAGCUGGAUGUACAAUAAAAAUGCUUGUUUCUUGGCCUUCCUUUAA